GCAGUCCCGGAUGAGGACGAGUAGAACGGUAACGGCCAUGGGGCGGUUGGCCUUCCUUCUACCAGACCUUGAUGUGGGAAGAGAGAAAUGGAGUAACAAGCCACAUUUGGCGCUUUGGAGAUGCCCACCACGCUUUGGGAAGAUGUACCAGCGUUUAUAGAAGGCCCGAGUGUAUAAGGAUAUAUUCCUAGACGUGGGACUGCUGGAUCAUAAGGGCACACCUUUCCCUCACCUUGACACCUCACAUUUCCCACCUCAUUCUAACAGCUAAAUUAGUGUCUAUAAGGAAUUUUCCAGACCUUCCGGGUUUCAUCAACUCUAUCUCCAAUUCAAUCCUCGUCUACACACACAGUUCAGGGGAGGCAAGAUAGCGGCUACAUUUUCUGUUCUUGACCUUCAGCUCCAAGGGACUGUUUCCCGGAUGCUUCGGACCGAGUGUUUGGUAGUGUCUGGGGAGGACUCGGUCAGGGAGCCCCCUCCUUUCACCCUGGUACUAGGAGCUGAAGAGGCGAGAUGCCAGGCGAACGGCUGAAGGCAGAGGUCUUUUUACCCCCAUCUCCCUUGUCUCCCACACAAGUUGUAGGGCCCCUCCACCGUGUCUGGUCCUGAAUUGGGAAUGCCAGCUCCCAGCGCGGCGAGGCCCAGGUCCGGUCCUAGGUGAGUUUUUCUCUCCGGCUGGAAGACUCGACGCCGUGGAUACCAGGGACCCGAGCCCUCCGGGGCUGCUGGCUUUGGAGGGAUUUCCAGACGUUGCAGUCGGGGUGAGCGGAGAGACUAAGAAGUACAGGGGACUAGAGAAAGCAGAUGAGGGUGAAUUGUCUCAUCAAGAUGGGGGAUAGGGAAAAGGGGCGAGAAGUAACCCGGGGCGCAAGGUCCACAGCGAAAAAAAAAAAAAAAAACAAACAAAAAAACAAACAAAAGAAACACGCCCGAGACCAAGGCUCAGCCACUUUACACGCAGGACUUGGUUGUGGCAGCGAGGAGGGCUUCGAACCUAGGAAAUUUUGAGGAAGCGUUUGUCUCCAUCACAGGAAUUGGGUUUCCACGUUGCUGCUGGAGCUUUUCGUAAGUCGAUAAGAGCAGCAUCUUUCUCUUUGUCUCCAAACCCGUGAAUUUGAUACGCUUUGAAAGCGUUCUUCUAGGCGAAAGAGCUUGGUACUUUCAUGCUUGGAUAGAAGGGGAGAGUUCAAUACCGUGCACGCGACCACAAAGUUGUUUUCGACGAGAAUUCGAUGGGAAGCGGAGGAACGAAUUUUUCCCACAUUCAGAGGCCAAGCCAGGAACUGUAAAACGUUCACCUUUGAAAGGUCCCACCGAGAUUCGAACUCGGAUUGCUGGAUUCAAAGUCCAGAGUGCUAACCAUUACACCAUGGGACCAACCACAAGGGUACAGUAGAGAUUUCUAAAAGAGAUGUUCUGAUUAUUCAAAGACUCUCUACUCAGAAAUGCCAAAAUGUGAGAAAUCAACAUGAGGACCACAGCAGAAGGAAACAGAGAAUGGAGAAGGGAACCAGGCAGCAAUUCAACAAAUAUUCCUUGGGCAUCUCUGCGCUACCAGAGGUCGCUGCGGUGAGCACCACGGGUCUGAGUGCCAGCGAUGGUUUAUCACGGUGACAGGAAAACACAGACCAGCAGCAUCUACUCCAGCACUACUCACACUGUGGAACUCUUUUCACCGUGAUGCCAGAUAACUAGGUAAUUCCGGAGUUAAUUCUCCGUCGUUUCCAGAGUACUUGCCUCCCCAGAAUUACUGGUACCGUAGGUGUUUGCACAACCAGUGAGAAGACGGCACCACCUGGAAUCCUAGAGCGGACCGGAAGUGAGCGUGGCUCACCGGGCCCGGCCGGAACCUACGGGCACAGCUGCGGGUGUGUCUGCGGAACCUCCACCUGAGCUGUAGAGUGUUUCCCUCGACCCACUAGUCUGGGUUCCACAGGGUCUGAGCUCCUCAGAGGUGGGAGCUGCGGCCGAGGGAAGGGUGCAUGUGCGCGGCGACAAUCGGGCCUCUUCCCCAGGCAGCUUGUGAGCCCCUCUCCCUCUCCGCCCUCGCCCAGGCUGCUCCGAUCUUCGUUUCCUUGCCUAGGCUCAUACACCCAGGCUUUAUUUAGGGCCAAAGUAUCCGUCAUAACCUCGGUUUUCUGUCUCGCAAGUAUCUUGCCGCUCAAUUUGUGACCCUGAAGCUUUAGUGAGUCGCUCUGUGCUCACUAUUUCUGGUCUUUUCAGAGGAUGGCUUCACUUUCAAUGGAAUUGCCCGAGUAACUGCCCUGUGUUGUCACGUAAACAAGUCCUUUUAAACUGAGUCUGUAGUUGUCCUGUGUUGAGUGUUUUCUUAUAUCAAAAACUUUCCUGACCAAGAACAAAAAAGGAGCUCAAGUAAAAUCACCCAUUUGCCUAGACCCCAACUGGAGAGAACCUUUGCCUGAGCUGUCUAAGCUCGGGAUGGAAGCAGUCUCUAGGGUCUUCCCAGCCUUGGCUGGCCAGGCUCCAGAAGAACAAGGGGAGAUUAUCAAAGUAAAGGUUAAAGAAGAAGACCACACUUGGGAUCAGGAAUCAGCCCUACGUAGGAAUUUGUCUUAUACCAGGGAACUCUCUCGUCAGCGCUUCAGGCAGUUCUGCUAUCAGGAGACACCUGGGCCCAGGGAGGCUCUGAGUCAACUGCGGGAACUUUGCCGUCAGUGGCUGAACCCAGAGAUACAUACCAAGGAGCAGAUCCUGGAAUUGUUGGUGCUGGAGCAGUUCCUGACCAUCCUGCCUGAGGAGCUCCAGUCUUGGGUGCGGGAGCAUAAUCCUGAGAGUGGAGAAGAGGUGGUGACUUUGCUGGAAGAUUUGGAGAGGGAGCUUGAUGAACCUAGACAGCAGGUCUCACAGGGCACAUAUGGGCAGGAAGUUUCUAUGGAAGAAAUGAUCCCUCUGGAUUCUGCAAAGGAGUCUUUAGGCACCCAGCUUCAGUCUAUGGAAGAUAGAAUGGAAUGUGAAUCUCCAGAGCCACACCCACUUCAAGAUAAUGGGUCAUUUUUGUGGUUUUCCAUGAUGUCUCAAAGCAUGGGUGGUGAUAACCUCAGUAGCUUAGAUACUAAUGAAGCAGAAAUUGAACCAGAAAACAUGAGAGAAAAGUUCUUCAGAAGCUUAGCAAGGUUACUGGAAAACAAAAGUAAUAAUACUAAGAUAUUUUCUAAAGCAAAGUACUGUCAGUUGAUAAAGGAAGUGAAAGAAGCUAAAGCUAAGGCGAAAAAGGAAUCAGUUGACUACCGUCGCUUGGCUAGAUUUGAUGUUAUCCUUGUACAAGGAAAUGAGAAGCUAAUUGAGGCUGUAAAUGGGGAAACAGAUAAAAUACGGUAUUACUUACACAGUGAGGACUUAUUUGACAUUCUGCAUAAUACACAUCUCAGCAUUGGACAUGGUGGACGUACUCGCAUGGAGAAAGAGUUACAAGCGAAAUACAAGAACAUCACAAAAGAAGUUAUAAUGCUGUAUCUGACCCUCUGUAAACCAUGCCAACAGAAAAAUUCAAAACUCAAGAAGGUUCUAACAUCAAAAUCAAUUAAGGAAGUUAGUUCAAGAUGCCAAGUAGAUCUUAUAGACAUGCAGUUGAAUCCUGAUGGGGAGUACAGAUUUAUUUUGCAUUAUCAAGAUCUCUGUACAAAGUUAACUUUUUUGCGGUCAUUAAAGUCUAAAAGGCCUACGGAAGUUGCACAUGCUCUUUUAGAUAUAUUUACAAUUAUUGGAGCACCCAGUGUCCUACAAUCUGACAAUGGGAGGGAAUUUUCAAGCCAGGUUGUCAGUGAACUCAGUAAUAUUUGGCCAGAAUUGAAAAUUGUCCAUGGGAAGUCUCAGACCUGCCAAAGCCAGAGUUCUGCAGAACAAACUGAGGAUAUCCGAAAGAGGAUUUUCUCCUGGAUGCAAACUAACAACUCAUCACACUGGACUGAAUUUUUGUGGUUCAUUCAGAUGUCCCAAAAUCAGCCCUAUCACAGAAGCAUGCAACAGACUCCAUGUGAAAGUGCAUUUAGCUCUGAAGCUAAACUGGGCUUGUCCCAUUCUCAGCUAACUGAAGAACUUGUUGCCAGCUUGCAUACAGAAAAUGAAUUAGAUCAGGCUGACAAAGAGUUAGAAAAUACUUUAAGAGCCCAGUAUGAAGAAAACAUUGAGACUGGAACAGACAGUAGUGAUAUUGAAGAGAAUCUUUCUGUCACUCCUAAGGUGGCUGAAAAAAGCCCUCCUGAGAGCAGACUAAGAUUUUUAUCCUGUGUAGUUUGUGAAAAAGAAUGCACAGGUGUUAAUAGUUGUAUAUCAUGUGAUGGAAAUAUCCAUGCAAUUUGUGGAGUGCCCUCUCAACAUGGGACUGAGGGCUGUGGUCGGCAAAUAACUUGUAGCCUUUGCUAUGAAACCAGCACAAUGAAGAGGAAACAUGAUGAGAUUCAAAGAAGUUUGCCUGUUAAACCUUCCAAAAUGCUAAAGCCAUCAGGGACACCAUUUUCACCAGACAAAGUAGGAGACUGGAUGGCGAAACAAGCUUCACUGGACUUUUUUGUCAAGAAAAGACAUGCCUUUUCUGAACACAGUAGUAGUAAUAAAAGAAAUGUUAACAAUAGAAGUUAUCCUGAAGAAGGGAAAACCAAAAGAGUUCAUGCUAGUUUCACUCGGAAAUAUGAUCCUUCAUAUAUUGAGUUUGGUUUUGUAGCUGUAAUUGAUGGUGAAGUACUAAAACCACAGUGUAUUAUUUGUGGAGAUGUACUGGCUAAUGAAGCAAUGAAACCAUCAAAACUUAAGCGACAUUUAUAUUCAAAACAUAAAGAAAUAAGUUCACAACCAAAAGAAUUCUUUGAAAGAAAGAGUAGUGAAUUGAAAAGCCAACCAAAGCAGGUGUUCAACGUUUCUCAUAUAAACAUUAGUGCUUUGCGGGCUUCAUAUAAAGUAGCACUUCCGGUUGCCAAGUCUAAAACACCAUACACAAUUGCUGAGACACUAGUGAAAGACUGCAUCAAAGAAGUUUGCUUGGAAAUGUUGGGUGAAUCUGCAGCAAAGAAGGUAGCUCAGGUACCACUUUCCAAUGACACCAUAGCUCGACGUAUUCAGGAACUGGCUAAUGAUAUGGAAGAUCAACUCAUAGAACAAAUAAAACUAGCAAAGUAUUUUUCAUUGCAACUUGAUGAAUGCAGAGAUAUUGCUAACAUGAUAAUUCUUUUAGUCUAUGUGAGGUUUGAACAUGAUGAUGAUAUAAAGGAAGAGUUCUUUUUUUCAGCCUCUUUGCCUACAAACACAACUAGCUCAGAACUGUAUGAAGCUGUAAAGAAUUAUAUUGUUAACAAAUGUGGUUUGGAAUUUAAAUUUUGUGUAGGAGUAUGUUCUGAUGGUGCAGCUUCAAUGACAGGAAAACAUUCUGAAGUGGUAACCCAGAUUAAGGAACUUGCGCCAGAAUGUAAAACAACACAUUGCUUCAUUCAUCGAGAAAGUCUUGCCAUGAAAAAAAUAUCAGCUGAACUAAAUAGUGUACUUAAUGAUAUAGUAAAAAUUGUGAAUUAUAUAAAAUCUAAUUCAUUGAAUUCAAGAUUAUUCUCUUUAUUAUGUGAUAAUAUGGAAGCUGAUCAUAAGCAACUGUUACUGCAUGCUGAGAUACGGUGGUUAUCACGGGGAAAAGUUCUGUCAAGAAUGUUUGAAAUACGAAAUGAACUCUUAGUGUUUCUGCAAGGCAAGAAACCCAUGUGGUCCCAACUUUUUAAAGAUGUGAAUUGGACAGCCAGACUUGCUUAUUUGUCUGAUAUCUUCAGUAUUUUUAAUGAUCUUAAUGCUUCUAUGCAAGGGAAGAAUGCAACUUAUUUUUCAAUGGCAGAUAAAGUUGAAGGACAAAAACAGAAGUUAGAAGCUUGGAAAAACAGAAUUUCUACAGAUUGUUAUGACAUGUUUCAUAAUUUAACAACAAUUAUCAAUGAAGUAGGUAAUGAUCUUGAUAUUGCACAUCUGCGAAAAGUUAUCAGUGAACAUCUUACAAAUUUGUUAGAAUGUUUUGAAUUUUAUUUUCCAUCAAAAGAAGAUCCACGCAUAGGAAAUUUGUGGAUCCAAAAUCCAUUUCUUUCAUCAAAAGAUAACUUAAAUUUAACUGUAACUCUACAGGAUAAGUUGUUGAAGCUGGCUACCGACGAAGGAUUGAAAAUCAGUUUUGAAAAUACAGCAUCACUUCCUUCAUUUUGGAUAAAAGCUAAAAAUGACUAUCCUGAGCUUGCUGAGAUUGCUUUAAAAUUGCUGCUUCUUUUCCCCUCAACAUACCUCUGUGAGACCGGAUUCUCUACUUUAAGUGUUAUUAAAACAAAACAUAGAAACAGUUUAAAUAUACAUUAUCCCCUGAGGGUAGCAUUGUCAUCAAUCCAACCUAGAUUAGACAAAUUAACAAGCAAGAAGCAAGCUCACUUAUCACAUUAAAAGCUUUAAAUAUUGAUAUGUAAGGUAUUGGUUCAAAGUAUGCAUAUAAGCAUUGAGUGUGAGGAAUUUGCUAUUUCACUUUAAACUUUCUGUCUAGUUACAGUUAUGGAAGUAUGAGAAGUUAUGAGUGAAACAGCAAUUUUCUAUAUAAAUUGCCUAUAUGUAUAUUUUCAAUUAAGAAUGUGUACAGUUUUUAUAAUUCUAUUUUUCCUCAUAUUUGUCGUAUUUAUUAAAAUAUAAUUUUAAAUCUGUUGAUUCUAAUAUUAAAACAUUUGAUCUUAUAUUUUGUGUCUUCUUCUUGUAUUUCAUUAGCAUGUUAAGAUUGUAGGACAACUUCAGGAUGGGAGAUGGUUUCUUUGAAAUAGACAAGGUCAGUGAAAGGAAGUGAAUUCAAAGGGGUAGGCUUAGAAUUCAAAUGCAGGGGACAGGUCAGUAGGGUAUGAAGUUUGUUAAACUGAUCCAGAGUGGUUAGGUUGGAAGUUGAUGUUGUUUGUUUUGUAGGUGCAUGUUUAGACAAAGAUGGAAGGGAACACUUAUUUUGUAAUGGUGUUAUGGCCUUGGAUUCAUAUUGAUAAAUUUAUUUACUUAUUUAUUUUUGAGGCAGGGUCUUGCUCUGUUGCCCAGGCUGGAGUGCAUUGGUGCAAUCUCUGCUCACUGCAACCUGUACCUCCUGGGUUCAAGUGAUUCUCUUGCCUCAGUCUUCCGAGUAACUGAGAUUACAGGCACCCACCACCAUGCCUGGCUAAUUUUUGUAUUUAUAGUAGAGAUGGGGUUUCACCAUGUUGGCCAGGCUCAUCUUGAACUCCUGACAUCAGAUGACCCUCCCACCUCGGCCUCUCAAAGUGCUGGGAUUACAGGCGUGACCUGCUGCGCCCGGCCGAUAAAUUCUGAUUUCAUAAGGAUGGGCGAUUGGGCCAUACUGACAAGUUUAUGUUAGGUGGUUUCUAGAUUUUGCUAGAACUGAUUGCCUUUAAGGUGCUCUGGGACAAAGUCAGAAAUUAUUGGCACCUCAAUUAGAUUUAACAACCUCUAUUUUGUUUGGAGAUGAUUCAGAAAAAUGCCACAAAUAUCUGCUCUUGUGUCUGUGAACUCAUUUAGAAUAAUCGAAAGCAAAUUAGUCCGAUAAAACAGGUUCUUUAGCAUCAAAACAUGACAGAAUCCAUGAAGAAAAUAUCUUUUCCUAGACAGGGUAGCAAUUUACAGUAAGUGCUUCGUUUCAAAUAAAUGUGAUAUUCAAAGUUAAGGAAAGGAAGGCUAUUUAGUGAUUCAGAAUGUUACUAAUAAUUUAACCUUUUGGUAAUGGAAGUUUCAAGGAUCCUCCAAACCUUUGAAAGUAGAGGAAAGGUUCAUAUUUAGUCCUGAAACCUUAAUUGGAU